GGCAGUUGGAAGAGAGAAGAAGUCACUACAGGGUACUGAGGAAAAGCUUUGCUGAAAUUGGAGAUCAAAUACCAGCUCUGCCAGUAAGAAGUUGCAUCUCCCAGUGAAAUGCUGCUGCUGCCAUUUCAACUGUUAGCUGUUCUCUUUCCUGGUGGUAACAGUGAACAUGCCUUCCAGGGGCCGACCUCCUUUCAUGUUAUCCAGACCUCGUCCUUUACCAAUAGUACCUGGGCACAAACUCAAGGCUCAGGCUGGUUGGAUGAUUUGCAGAUUCAUGGCUGGGAUAGCGACUCAGGCACUGCCAUAUUCCUGAAGCCUUGGUCUAAAGGUAACUUUAGUGAUAAGGAGGUUGCUGAGUUAGAGGAGAUAUUCCGAGUCUACAUCUUUGGAUUCGCUCGAGAAGUACAAGACUUUGCCGGUGAUUUCCAGAUGAAAUACCCCUUUGAGAUCCAGGGCAUAGCAGGCUGUGAGCUACAUUCUGGAGGUGCCAUAGUAAGCUUCCUGAGGGGAGCUCUAGGAGGAUUGGAUUUCCUGAGUGUCAAGAAUGCUUCAUGUGUGCCUUCCCCAGAAGGUGGCAGCAGGGCACAGAAAUUCUGUGCACUAAUCAUACAAUAUCAAGGUAUCAUGGAAACUGUGAGAAUUCUCCUCUAUGAAACCUGCCCCCGAUAUCUCUUGGGCGUCCUCAAUGCAGGAAAAGCAGAUCUGCAAAGACAAGGAAAGAUGCAACUGUCCUAUUUCCUAAUAGUUGGGUUAAGGUCAUGGACUGAGUUCUGGGCAAUGGAAUGUGUGGUGUUGGAAGCAUUAGCCAGCUCCAGUCCUGACCACUGAAAAUAUCACAUCUGAUCAUCUUACCCUGUGGUACCAACUUGGCAGUCAAAUUUCUAAAUGGCAAGACUAUGAGAUGGAGAAGAGCAGCCUGAUCUACAUGCAGUUUAACUGCAUGAGAAAUAAACUUCAUUGUGUUAAGCCUCCAAGUUCUAAAGUUUAUUUAUAACUGCAACAUAACCUAGCUAUAUUGGAUAAUAUUAUAAAACCCAGUAAGUAUCAUCCUUUUUGCCCUCUUGAAUUCAGAAGCAAACAAGUUGAAAAUAACAUGAGAUAGAUGGAUCUAAUGGUCAAUCUUGACUUCUGAUAGUGCCACUAGAUAAUUUGCUUUAAGUGUGUAAUCCAAGUGAUCUUGCUCAUACUGGACCCUAAAUGGAGUGGCCUUCUCAUUGUUAUGGACUGAAAGUUUGUGUACCCUCCCAAAGAAAAAAAAAAUCACAUGUUGAAUCCCUAACUCUCAGUGUGAUUAUAUUUGGAAAUGGGGCCUCUAAGAAGUAAUGUCAAUCUCAUGUCUAAACGGUAAGACCCUGAUCCAAUAGGCUUAGUGUCCUUAUAAGAAGAGACACUGGAGUGCCCUUCCACUUUCCUUCUCUGUCUCUCUGUCUCUCCCUGUCGCUCUCUGUCUCUGUGUGUGUGUGUGUGUGUGCACCCACCAUGGAAAGGCCAUAUGAGCUCAUAGUGAGAAGGCAGUUGUCUGUAUAAACCAGGAAGAGAACCUUCACUAGAAACUGAGUCUUCCAGAUGGAGACUUUGAACUUCUAGCCUCUAGAGCUGUGAGAGAAUAACUUCCUGUUGUUUAAGCCACCCAGCUGAUUGCCUUGUGUUAGCACAGCCCAAGAAGACUAAUACACUCACUUAUUUCAGGCAAUGCUGAUAAAACCCUAAGUUCCCCACCUGAGCAGCUGUUCCUGUGAGAGCCAGGGCCUGGAGGAGGAGAGCAAGACUGAGCCUUUGGGGAGCAACUUGCCCAGAGAGGUAAAGGGCAGUAGGAGGUGCUGAUAUAUACUUGCCCAGUUUCCCUCCUGAAUUUAUCAGUGAGAUAAAUCAGUCUGUUUUCAGAGGAAAGAUUAAGGGGUGAGGAAAAAAAAACAAAAAGUAUUUAUGGGAAAUUCCCCCUCAGGGUGCCUAGAAGAGUAAGUAACACCCUCACCCCCAUCAUGGCAAUACGCAUUCAAAUAGAUACCUAGAAAUGUGUGUUCUCCGAAAACUUCCCUCUCCUUUGCUCCACACAGUCACCAUGUCAUUUCUCUCCCUCCACCUGGUUUUUCCUCUCUGAUCUGACUGAUAUGUAGUCCUGCUUUCAUCCUGUGGGACAGAGAUCACAGCCACAGUCCCUGCCGGUGUGUCACAGUCCAUAUCCCUCCAUGUCCAUGCAGUGCUCUGCCCCAGAGCUGCCAUGGAAAACGUGAUCCUUAGAAUGUCUAUCAGCCUAAAAUAUUCAAAUUGCUUUCAUGAAAAAUAACCCAGACUCCUAAGUAUGACAAUUUUAUACACAAGAGUUUAUGUACAUCUAUCCCUAAAAAGGAAGGGUGGAGGUAGUGUAAGAAGGGAAACUGGCAGACUCUUUACACUGGUGAAUACUUAUAAAUAUAGAUGCAAGAAUCUGAAAUUGAUAUAAAAUGCAAUGGGGAGAGGAGUAAGUGGUUAUUAAGCUCUCUGAACACACAAAAUCCUAAGAGAAUAAUCUGAAGUGGGUAGGACACCCUAUGAUUAGAACCCAGCCUGAACAGAGGGGCUGGGUUGUCCCGAGGGAGCCCAGUGCUCUUCCUGUCCUUCCCCAACUUCCCUUUUCUUGUCCUUUUGCUCAGACCACAGACGUUGUUGUGUUUGCCUUCGCCUGGGCUCUUCUUGCCUGUCACUUCCCUAAGACCACUCUAGUGGGUGACUUUUGCACCCCGAGAGAGAGAGAGAUUUCCUCAGAACUCCAGUGUCAUGUUCCCACCCCACACAGCUCUGUCAUCCCUUCCUCCCAGCAGAAACCUUGCCCUCUGCCUACUUCCCCAUUACGGAAACCCCACAAGCCUCCCACAGCCACGUGACUCUUACAUGGCCUUUCAUUUCCUCCUCAACUCUUAUUGAAGUGAUUCACUCCUUCUUUCUGGCCUCCAAGCAUAGUUCCUGUGGCUAGCGUAUAUCCUCCACCCUCUGCCCUCUGCAACAGCCAAAAAGGUCCCAGUCUGAGAGCUAUGAAAACUCCUAGAUUUACCACUUACUAGAAGCACUAAUUCCCCACUGUAAAAUGACAAAAUUGGAGGAACUUGAUAUUUUCUAGUUCCAUUUCAACUUUAAUAUUAUUUGACUUGUCCUGUGCUUCUGUUCAUUUCUGUUUAUACAGUAUUUUCUGUCUCUUCUGGGCUUCUUUGUCUUAAUGUUUAACUUUUCUAUGAUCUCAUAUUGCUUUCUACUUAUCCUUUGUUUGAAUCCCUUGGGUCUCCUCUCUAUCUUAUCACCAAUUCUACCUAAACUCCCUACCCAUUCAUUCUAAGCACCACCCUGGCUAAAUUUUGAAGCCUAAAAUAUUGCUU